UGGGCUGGUGGUCUCUUCACAAUGAGGCCAGCGGUUGUCUAACACAAGGCAGGCUCUGAUGCACGCCCAUGUCCAUGGUCACACUGACUCCUUCCUGCUACUCCAUGAGAUGACCCAGCUGAUAUCACUGCCCCCACUUUACACAUGAGGAAGCUGAGGCCAGGGAGAGGAGGCAACUUUUCCACAGUCACACAGCUUGCCAGGGGCUCACCAGGAAUCAACCCAGGCCCUAGCUGUCCCAGGCCAUUCCUCUUUCUGACUCAGCCACUGCCCUUCAACUCAAAGUUUUCUCUCCCAGGAGAAAAAAAAAAAAAAAAGGACUUCCUGUCUUUUUCCUGAUUUUGAAAUAAUAACAACAAUAGCUAACAUUCAGAUAUCUUCGAUAAUGUUCACCAUGUGUGAGGCACAUUUGGACUCAUUUAAUCCUCACAACACCCAUAUGGGAUUUAACCAUUUAACAGAUAGGAAAUGACAGCAUACAGAGGUGAGGGGACCUGCCCGGGGUCACUCAGCUCACAAGGAGCAGGGCUUGGCGUCCAGUUCAUGCAGGCUAUGGCCUCCCUUUAACCACCAUGCAGCACUGCCCUUCGGAAAUGCAAGCUUUUCCUCGCCAAAGAGCUUUCAGGCAUAUUCUGGAACAGGGAGAUGCUGUGAACAGCCCCCAGCCUCCGAAGCCCUCCUAAAAUCUACUCGUGUGUGUUUGCAUGCAUGUGUGUAUCUGCUUAUGUGUGUGCAAAUGUGUAUCCACUAAGCACACACACCAGUCCACUAAAGUGCUCCCACUUGUCCUAAAGGUCAGACAGCAGCUGGGUCAUUGCUUGCUCUGCUCUCAGAAGGGAGAAAAAGUUCCAUUUUGGCUGACAAGCUGCAAUUCUAGGCUUUGCCCUGGAGGACUGGACUUCCCUAGGGCCAGGACCCUGGGCCUCCCUCCUUCGAGGAGCGGGGUCUCCACCCCAGAGCAGUGGGGUGGGUCUCCCUGGGAGAUGGGGGAUGGGAAGGGCAGCAGGGUCUCACUGGGCGGGAAUGGCAGAGGUUCAAGAGAUAAGCUGAUGGAUGAAAAGGUCAGCAUCCAAAAGAAAGCCCAAAGAACUCCCCAGGGCAGCCAGCUGUCUGUCACAUGGUCCCGGAGGCUCCCGCUGUCCACAUCUGCAUCAGCACCAUGGGUGGGAAGUUCAAAACCCAGCAUAGCCGGGGCCCAAACUUCAGUGAGGAAAUCGUCUAAGGGAAGAGGGUGCCUGGUUGGUGGCAUAUGGUUCCAGGUCAUCAGCACCCUGAGAACACAGGCUUCUGAAACUGGCCAACCUGGAGUCCCCUUCCAGCUGUACAAAUUCUUUGCUGUGUGUCCAUGCGGAGUUCACAUCCUCUCUCUGAGCCUCAGUUUACUCGUGUGUAAAGCAAGGAGGCUGGACUCGACAACCCUUAGGAUCCAUUCCAGGUCUAAUCUGUUUCCGAACCUUUAAUGCGCACCUAGAGUGUACCAAACACUGUACUAUUUAUUGGGGAUAUGGUGGGGAACAAGAGGCCAAGGAAGGGGACAGUAAUCGGGUAGGCAAAUUAAGAAGCAGGAUAGUUUUAGGCAGGGAUCAAUGCUGUGCAAUAAACCAGGUGCUGUAAUAAGAGUGGCUAGGGGGUGAUGGAAGUGGAGAGGGAUUUCUACCAUAGAAGGUGAUCAGGGAAGGCUUCUCUGAGCAGGUAGUUUUUGAGAAGGUUACAGGUGGGGGCGGAGCACUCCAGACAAAGGAGGAGCAAGUGCAAACGCCCUAAGGUAGGAACAAGUCUGCCCUGUUGGAGAAGAUAAAGAAAGGCCAUGUGGUUGGGACAGAGGCAAUGAGGUUGGGGUGUGGUGGAAGAGUGGGCAGUCUUCUCAGGGCUUCAGCCACCAAGAGAAGCUCCUGGUCCAGGCAGGGACGUGGAUUCGUGAACCAAUCUUUUUUUUUCUCUGUUGCAAUGUGGACCCCAUUUCUCUCCAGAGGGAGGAGGAGACAUAAAGCCAUGAGACCCUGGAAAGCAUUUCUGAGCUGGGGCACAAGCCUAGGAGGCAGUGGGUAGCAAAGUGAGUUGGGAUGGAGGAAAAUUACUCUUCAUUUGAGGUGUGGUUCUCUCUCUCCCACUGAGAAGAAAAUGCAUGGCAGAAAGAACAUCUGUCAGUUUUGCCCCACAGUGGAAAAUGCAAGGCUGGGAAACCUGAGUCCUGGGUUUUCCUACGGCCGUUCCAGGCACUGGGCAGCACGAUGCCAGGAAUGUUCUUUCCUUUUUCUCCAGGGAAGGCUAAGUGGGUGUCAGCCAUUCACACCUCUGUGGGAAAGACUCUACCACUGGCACUGUCCUUCCAACACCUGGAUAAAGUCAGGGUUUUCAAUGAGGGGCAGGGGCUGGGGGAGGUGAUGUGAUUCUCAAAGCCAGGGCCUGUGUAGGGAGAUAUCUGGGCCCGGGACCCUCACCCAGACCUGCUGAGGAAGGCGUGAGUCUCUCCCGCUCACAGAGGGGUUGGGCAAAGACUUGAACCUGAGUCUGUCUAACUCCAACACAGGGAUUUUUCCUCCCCUGCCCCUCUGUCUCAGCCAGCUGCACAGUUUCACUACAAACAUCAGUCCCAGGGGAGAGGGAGGAAGGAGAGGGGCAGGGUGGUGAGGUCUGCGUUCCUUAAAUAAACGGAGGGCAGAAUUCUAGCCAGAAGGGGGCGAGGGUUACCCAGCCCAGUGGAGCAUGGAGCCGCCCCUCUAGUUCCCACUGCCACCGUGAUGCCAUCAGAUGGGAGAAAACACAGAACUCGGGAUGAAACGUCACACGGUCUGGGCUAAAGAUCUUGCUCUUUAAUUUCCCAGCAGGUAACCUUGUGGCAGUCACUAACCCUCUCUACACCUCAAUGUUCUCAUCUGUAAAAUGGAAAUGAUGACCCCUGGGUCUCCCAGGACCGUGAGGGGUCCUGAAAGGGCAGGUGUGCGCGGUGCUUUGUAGAUGAUAAGGCAUCUCAGAAACACCGGGGCUUUACUGUUAUUUUCUCUCCAGCUUGUUUGGGCAGACAAAAGAGAAAUCGAGCCCAGUCAUUCUUAGCACAGCCAAGAAGGGCAGAUUUCAAAAGGAGCCUUGCUUCAAACUGAGGAAAACCAAAAAGGAAAAAACAACAAACACAGCUGCCCCUACCCUCCAGUCCACAAAACAGUCUGUGUCUGACAAGCUGGGCUCUGCCAGCGGCCCACCCCCAGACUCCUGCACCAGCUGGCCUUCCUGACCUGUGUGCCCUGGGAGCCAGGCCGACUCUUCACACUUCCAGUCACCGACACAGUGCAAUGCAACCCAUUCUUGCUCAAGGCCUCCUUAGAAAUUAUUCCUCCCAUUGCUCGAACCUGGGAGUUGGAGAUUGCAGUGAGCCACGAUGGUGCCACUCCACUCUAGCCUGGGUGACACAGUGAGACCCUGCCUCAAAAAAAAGAAAAGAAAAGGGAGGGGAGGGAAGGGAAAAUUAAAAAAAAAGAAAAGAGAAAAGAAAAGAAAUUACUCCUUCCCCAGGCAGGGAAGCCACCCAGAGCUGUCCACACUGCAUAUUAGGGCUUGCACACUCUAGCUCCCCAGCCUCUCCCACUCCCUCUUCCUGUACACGUGCACACACACACACACACACACACACACCCCAACACACUUCUGGGGAAUUCAGACUCACUUCCUUUCCUUCGGUGGCCUCCAGGAUGAUCUGGUAAAACCUUAAGCGAUGCAAUUUUUUUAUGAUUCUAAUCUGCCGCAGAGCUGACCCUCUCCCUAUUCCCAGCAGGCUGAUAACCCAGCUCCUAAGCACCUCUCUUGGCAGCCUCCUUCAGAAUGGCAUUCCUGGGCAAGGCCUGGCAGCUCUGGAAGGCUCUCGUUGAGUUGGCUCUGUUACCCAUGAGAGGAAACUCUCAGCUGUCACAUGUUGAUUGUUCAGAUGAGCAGAGAAGUGGGCACAGAAAGAGUUGGGCACAGGACUGGUUAAGUGUGGAUGGGGGUCAACUUGGAAGAAAGCGUAGCGGGGAUACUGCACAAAGGAAGCCAGCCCAGGAAGGGUCACCCUGUCCAACGUGUCCGAGCGGAAAGACAACAUGCGCCUCGGCCUUAGUCUCGCCACCAACCCCAAGGACAACAGCUUCCUGGCCUGCAGCCCCCUCUGGUCUCAUGAGUGUGGGAGCUCCUACUACACCACAGGGAUGUGUUCAAGAGUCAACUCCAACUUCAGGUUCUCCAAGACCGUGGCCCCAGCUCUCCAAAGGUGCCAGACCUACAUGGACAUCGUCAUUGUCCUGGAUGGCUCCAACAGCAUCUACCCCUGGGUGGAGGUUCAGCACUUCCUCAUCAACAUCCUGAAAAAGUUUUACAUUGGCCCAGGGCAGAUCCAGGUUGGAGUUGUGCAGUAUGGCGAAGAUGUGGUGCAUGAGUUUCACCUCAACGACUACAGGUCUGUAAAAGAUGUGGUGGAAGCUGCCAGCCACAUUGAGCAGAGAGGAGGAACAGAGACCCGGACGGCAUUUGGCAUUGAAUUUGCACGCUCAGAGGCUUUCCAGAAGGGUGGAAGGAAAGGAGCCAAGAAGGUGAUGAUUGUCAUCACAGAUGGGGAGUCCCACGACAGCCCAGACCUGGAGAAGGUGAUCCAGCAAAGCGAAAGAGACAACGUAACAAGAUAUGCGGUGGCCGUCCUGGGCUACUACAACCGCAGGGGGAUCAAUCCAGAAACUUUUCUAAAUGAAAUCAAAUACAUCGCCAGUGACCCUGAUGACAAGCACUUCUUCAAUGUCACUGAUGAGGCUGCCUUGAAGGACAUUGUCGAUGCCCUGGGGGACAGAAUCUUCAGCCUGGAAGGCACCAACAAGAACGAGACCUCCUUUGGGCUGGAGAUGUCACAGACGGGCUUUUCCUCGCACGUGGUGGAGGAUGGGGUUCUGCUGGGAGCCGUCGGUGCCUAUGACUGGAAUGGAGCUGUGCUAAAGGAGACGAGUGCCGGGAAGGUCAUUCCUCUCCGCGAGUCCUACCUGAAAGAGUUCCCCGAGGAGCUCAAGAACCAUGGUGCAUACCUGGGGUACACAGUCACAUCGGUCGUGUCCUCCAGGCAGGGGCGGGUGUACGUGGCCGGAGCCCCCCGGUUCAACCACACGGGCAAGGUCAUCCUGUUCACCAUGCACAACAACCGGAGCCUCACCAUCCACCAGGCUAUGCGGGGCCAGCAGAUAGGCUCUUACUUUGGGAGUGAAAUCACCUCGGUGGACAUCGACGGCGACGGCGUGACUGAUGUCCUGCUGGUGGGCGCACCCAUGUACUUCAACGAGGGCCGUGAGCGAGGCAAGGUGUACGUCUAUGAGCUGAGACAGAACCUGUUUGUUUAUAACGGAACGCUAAAGGAUUCACACAGUUACCAGAAUGCCCGAUUUGGGUCCUCCAUUGCCUCAGUUCGAGACCUCAACCAGGAUUCCUACAAUGACGUGGUGGUGGGAGCCCCCCUGGAGGACAACCACGCAGGAGCCAUCUACAUCUUCCACGGCUUCCGAGGCAGCAUCCUGAAGACACCUAAGCAGAGAAUCACAGCCUCAGAGCUGGCUACCGGCCUCCAGUAUUUUGGCUGCAGCAUCCACGGGCAAUUGGACCUCAAUGAGGAUGGGCUCAUCGACCUGGCAGUGGGAGCCCUUGGCAACGCUGUGAUUCUGUGGUCCCGCCCAGUGGUUCAGAUCAAUGCCAGCCUCCACUUUGAGCCAUCCAAGAUCAACAUCUUCCACAGAGACUGCAAGCGCAGUGGCAGGGAUGCCACCUGCCUGGCCGCCUUCCUCUGCUUCACGCCCAUCUUCCUGGCACCCCAUUUCCAAACAACAACUGUUGGCAUCAGAUACAACGCCACCAUGGAUGAGAGGCGGUAUACACCGAGGGCCCACCUGGACGAGGGCGGGGACCGAUUCACCAACAGAGCCGUACUGCUCUCCUCCGGCCAGGAGCUCUGUGAGCGGAUCAACUUCCAUGUCCUGGACACUGCUGACUACGUGAAGCCAGUGACCUUCUCAGUCGAGUAUUCCCUGGAGGACCCUGACCAUGGCCCCAUGCUGGACGACGGCUGGCCCACCACUCUCAGAGUCUCGGUGCCCUUCUGGAACGGCUGCAAUGAGGAUGAGCACUGUGUCCCUGACCUUGUGUUGGAUGCCCGGAGUGACCUGCCCACGGCCAUGGAGUACUGCCAGAGGGUGCUGAGGAAGCCUGCGCAGGACUGCUCCGCAUACACGCUGUCCUUCGACACCACAGUCUUCAUCAUAGAGAGCACACGCCAGCGAGUGGCGGUGGAGGCCACACUGGAGAACAGGGGCGAGAACGCCUACAGCACGGUCCUAAAUAUCUCGCAGUCAGCAAACCUGCAGUUUGCCAGCUUGAUCCAGAAGGAGGACUCAGACGGUAGCAUUGAGUGUGUGAACGAGGAGAGGAGGCUCCAGAAGCAAGUCUGCAACGUCAGCUAUCCCUUCUUCCGGGCCAAGGCCAAGGUGGCUUUCCGUCUUGAUUUUGAGUUCAGCAAAUCCAUCUUCCUACACCACCUGGAGAUCGAGCUCGCUGCAGGCAGUGACAGUAAUGAGCGGGACAGCACCAAGGAAGACAACGUGGCCCCCUUACGCUUCCACCUCAAAUACGAGGCUGACGUCCUCUUCACCAGGAGCAGCAGCCUGAGCCACUACGAGGUCAAGCCCAACAGCUCGCUGGAGAGAUACGAUGGUAUCGGGCCUCCCUUCAGCUGCAUCUUCAGGAUCCAGAACUUGGGCUUGUUCCCCAUCCACGGGAUGAUGAUGAAGAUCACCAUUCCCAUCGCCACCAGGAGCGGCAACCGCCUACUGAAGCUGAGGGACUUCCUCACGGACGAGGCGAACACGUCCUGUAACAUCUGGGGCAAUAGCACUGAGUACCGGCCCACCCCAGUGGAGGAAGACUUGCGUCGUGCUCCACAGCUGAAUCACAGCAACUCUGAUGUCGUCUCCAUCAACUGCAAUAUACGGCUGGUCCCCAACCAGGAAAUCAAUUUCCAUCUACUGGGGAACCUGUGGUUGAGGUCCCUAAAAGCACUCAAGUACAAAUCCAUGAAAAUCAUGGUCAACGCAGCCUUGCAGAGGCAGUUCCACAGCCCCUUCAUCUUCCGUGAGGAGGAUCCCAGCCGCCAGAUCGUGUUUGAGAUCUCCAAGCAAGAGGACUGGCAGGUCCCCAUCUGGAUCAUUGUAGGCAGCACCCUGGGGGGCCUCCUACUGCUGGCCCUGCUGGUCCUGGCACUGUGGAAGCUCGGCUUCUUUAGAAGUGCCAGGCGCAGGAGGGAGCCUGGUCUGGACCCCACCCCCAAAGUGCUGGAGUGAGGCUCCAGAGGAGACUUUGAGUUGAUGGGGGCCAGGACACCAGUCCAGGUAGUGUUGAGACCCAGGCCUGUGGCCCCACCGAGCUGGAGCGGAGAGGAAGCCAGCUGGCUUUGCACUUGACCUCAUCUCCCGAGCAAUGGCGCCUGCUCCCUCCAGAAUGGAACUCAAGCUGGUUUUAAGUGGAACUGCCCUACUGGGAGACUGGGACACCUUUAACACAGACCCCUAGGGAUUUAAAGGGACACCCCUACACACACCCAGGCCCAUGCCAAGGCCUCCCUCAGGCUCUGUGGAGGGCAUUUGCUGCCCCAGCUACUAAGGUGCUAGGAAUUCGUAAUCAUCCCCAUCCUCCAGAGAAACCCAGGGAGGAAGACUGUAAAUACGAACCCAAUCUGCACACUCCAGGCCUCUAGUUCCAGAAGGAUCCAAGACAAAACAGAUCUGAAUUCUGCCCUUUUCUCUCACCCAUCCCACCCCUCCAUUGGCUCCCAAGUCACACCCACUCCCUUCCCCAUAGAUAGGCCCCUGGGGCUCCCGAAGAAUGAACCCAAGAGCAAGGGCUUGAUGGUGACAGCUGCAAGCCAGGGAUGAAGAAAGACUCUGAGAUGUGGAGACUGAUGGCCAGGCAAGUGGGACCAGGAUACUGGACGCUGUCCUGAGAUGAGAGGUAGCCGGGCUCUGCACCCACGUGCAUUCACAUUGACCGCAACUCACACAUUCCCCCACCAGCUGCAGCCCCUUGCUCUCAGCUGCCAACCCUCCCGGGUCACUUUUGUUCCCAGGUACCUCAUGGGAAGCAUGUGGAUGACACAAUCCCUGGGGCUGUGCAUUCCCACGUCUUCUUGCUGCAGCCUGCCCCUAGACAUGGACGCACCGGCCUGGCUGCAGCUGGGCAGCAGGGGUAGGGGUAGGGAGCCUCCCCUCCCUGUAUCACCCCCUCCCUACACACACACACACACACACACACACACACACACACACACACACACACACACACACACACUGCCUCCCAUCCUUCCCUCAUGCCCGCCAGUGCACAGGGAAGGGCUUGGCCAGCGCUGUUGAGGGGUCCCCUCUGGAAUGCACUGAAUAAAGCACGUGCAAGGACUCCCGGAGCCUGUGCAGCCUUGGUGGCAAAUAUCUCAUCUGCCGGCCCCCAGGACAAGUGGUAUGACCAGUGAUAAUGCCCCAAGGACAAGGGGCGUGCCUGGCGCCCAGUGGAGUAAUUUAUGCCUUAGUCUUGUUUUGAGGUAGAAAUGCAAGGGGGACACAUGAAAGGCAUCAGUCCCCCUGUGCAUAGUACGACCUUUACUGUCGUAUUUUUGAAAAAUUAAAAAUACAGUGUUUAAAAACAACCAAGCACUGACAUCCCAUUCUGUGGGCAGAGCAUAUCACAGUGAGCCAUACUCCCCUUUGAAGGAGAGGAAGUAGAAUGAGGGAGUUCCUUGCUUCCUCCCCCCUACCUCUACAUGUCAGAAGGGACUCAUCCACCAUUUGCUGCCCACAACAUGCCCUCCUAGUGGCUGCCUGGCCUCCGUGUGACGUCUCCAGUGGUGGAGCGCUCCCUCUCCCAAGAUCACCCUUCCAUCUAUGGCCAGUGUGGACGGUUAGGACCUAAAUGUUUCACUGUAGCUUCUGCCCUUGGUUCCAGCUCUUCCCUCUCACGCCUCCCAGACUUCUCCAGGCCGGUUUCAUUGUUAACCGUCUUACACUCUGACAUCAGCCAAGGCGUCUCCAUUCUGUUCUUGUGCCAUUCAUGUCUUGGAUUCCCAGUAAGUAGAACCUUGGAAAUAAUUUGAUCUUGUUUUUGCAUAAAUGAGGACACUCAGAACCAGGAAGAGCCCUAGGCUCCCACAGCAAAACCAAAACUAAACCCAGGACUGCUAUUUCCCAAGCCAGAUUCUGUUAUUCGAGCCCAGCCUUAGAAGGGCUUGAUGUGGAGCAAAAGGUGAAAAUGGUGAAACUAAAAUUUGAGUAUCAAAACCCAUUGCCUUCUAAUAGAAUCAGAAGGAAAUGUUGCUAAAUCAUAUUCCAUUUCCGUCAUCACUCUUAUGAAUGGGGUAACCUGGCUAAAUGAGAAUUAAUGAACCCACACUCAUAAGUUUUCAUUGACUUAGCACCAAGUCGUCCAUCAAAUAUCAUCAGAUCUGAGAAUGCUCUUAUGGAUAUCUGAUUUUUAGAGGCUGGCAUUCAUAUUUUUAAAAACUGCCACCUGUGACCACACUGCAGGCCAAACAGAAUGUACCUGCUGGUCAGAUGCAGCCCAGAGGUCACUGAAUUGCAACCUCUGGACUCUCGGUCAGAGGCAAGCAGCCCUUAUUCCAGAACUCCACAGUCCUUCACACCCUUCCCCAGACCUACACCAAGACCAACUAAGUGGUCAAAAGGUGGACAAACUGAGAGUUGUAUCAAGGCCCUUAGCCUCUCAAUUUGUUAUCAAGUUUCCCUUUCUGAAUCUAUUUACCCUGAAGUAUAAAUACCCAAGAUGAGCCUUAAGAGUGCCUGGUAGAGCAAACAAAGAUGCAUCUUAUAGGGAGCAAAGUCUAUGCUAACGCAGUGUUUCUCAAUCCUGGCUGCACCUUUGAACCACGGGAGCUUUAAAAGUGACCACUGCAAGGGCCCUACCCACUAUGGAUCCCAAUUUCAUUGGUUGGGAGAGGGGCCAAGUUUGUUUCCAACUUCCCCAGAUGACUCUAAUGGCUGAGAGUUGCAAUCAACAGGUAAGUGAAUAUCCAGGCUGUAAGAUGAAGAAAGAGGGGGUUGUGCCCAAGCCCACUGUGCCUCAUAAAGCAGAUGAUCUCUGCAGCGCUGCGCUUCUCAAAGAGUGGUCCCAGGACUGCCUCAGUCAGACCACAGACUCCUAAGUUCCUCCUCAGACUUCAUGGAUCCAAGCUCUGUGAGGUAAUUCUAAGCACAUUAAACUUGUAGAACAGCCAUCUGGAUUUAAUAUUACAUAAUAGCUAUAAUAUUCUGCUAUUCUCUAAUCUUCAAUGUCAGUUUCUUAAACUGUCAGGCCUGUCUUUAGAUGCCCUUCAACUGUGCUGGGGACUAUCUUGAUGGCAGCCAGCAAAGAAAAUCAGCAAAAACCCCAGUGGAGUUUCUGGGUUUUACUUUUGUUAAGGAAGGUGAUGGUUUCUUGACAUGACAGGUAUCUAGGUGGAAAGGGCAAAGUGCUAAUGCAAACACAAUGGAGACACUAUGGAAUAGCUCUGCCUAGGGACAUGUGGAAGAGCUUCUAGGAGACAGUGUGGACCUUUCCAUCCCUAGAGGUCUUCACAAGAUAAAUUCCUACCUCCGUCAGUAUUCAAAAGGUUUUAGCAUCAAUACUGUCUGAGAAUAAGACAUUAGACUUGAGUCAGUCCCCUGGCUUCAAUCCCAGGAUGCCAAGCAGCCUCUAAUGGAGACCGCUGGCUUAAUCGUGCUCCUUUCCUGGCAUAACAACUCACUGCACCCAUGCCUCACCACCACGAAGCAGUCUCCUCACCACCCAAAUGUGCCUUGGGUGACUUAAAUACAGCCAUUAGUAUGAAUGGUCCCCUGUUUUUAUUCAACACCACACCAGUCUUUGCUUUUACCUUCGGCUAAUGUGGUUCCAGCCUUUUAUCCUGCACUCCUUCUUAUAAUUUAAAAAAAAAAAAAACUCCCCUACUAUCUUUAUGUUAAUAUUAACAUCAACUAGGUUCUUCUCAAAGGACAGCCAGGCCUAACUGGCCACGUUAAAAUCUGCACAGUGCUUUUGUGUCACUGUCUAUUCUAUUAGUUUCAACAUCAUGCUAAAAUAGGACAGCAUGUUCCAAAACUGAAACUGAAACAGGAACGGAGCCUUGCUGAUUUAGCAUGAGGAGGGAAUUGUAAGCCUUGCACCUGGACACUAAAACUUUUCAAUAAGAUGUAUGCUAAGCCGUACCUAGCAAACUUACCAGGUCCAAAGUAGAGUACAAGCAGAAAGUUAUUUUUAAAGGAUGGGCACUAUCCUUGAGGGACUUACCCUUUCUAAUCAGCUUUGCAUGGUUUGUUUUGAGACAGUGUCUCACUCUGUUGCCCAGGCUAGAGUGCAGCGGCACCAUCACAGCUCACGGCAGCCUCUGCCUCCCGGGCUCAAGCAAUCCCACCUCAGUUUCCCAAGUAGCUGGGACUACAGGCACACACCACACUCAGCUAAUUUUAGUAUUUUUUGUAGAGACAGGGUCUCGCCAUGUUGCCCAGGCUGGUCUCAAACUCCUGGAUUAUCUCCCUGGCCCUGCAUUAAAAAAGAUGUGCAACAACUUAGUGAUGUGUCUGAAAUGUUUUCAGAAGGUGGCCCAAGUCAGAGUCAAAAAAUUUUUUUAUUUGGAAAAUUAGAGGAAAUACAGAAAAUCAAAUUUCAAAUAGAUGCAUCUAAAUGGAGAACAAGCUUAUCAAGGACAGAGUCCAUCUUUCUUAUUUUUAUUUUUGAGACAGGGUCUUGCUCUGUCACCCAGGCUAGAGUGCAGCGGCACAAUCACAGCUCCCUGCAGCCUCGACCUCCUGGACUUCAGUGAUCCUCCCACCUCAGCCUCUUGAGUAGCUGGGACUACAGACAUGCACCACCAUGCCCAGCUAAUUUUUUUUUUAAUUUUGUGCAGAGAGGGGGUCUCACUUUGUUGCCCACACUGGUCUCUCUUAUUUUUGUAUGCAUAUCUGUGGUGCAGUGCCUGAAAUACAGUAGGUGUUCAAUAAGCGCCAACAUGCAAGAGUAUCUUGCCAUUGAUUAAGGCAAAAGCAAAACCCCAGUCCGCCCCUCUGAUGGACUGAGCACACCAAAUUUCUAAAGCACAGGCAAAUUAGAAAAUAUAAUUUUGUCUAAACUUGCCAACAAGCUAAGGUUUUGUGAACCACCUAAAAUUUGCCUCUCUCAUACUGAAAUUUUCUAGGUCAAGUAUCUGAAGGAAUACACUACUGCCAGUAUUUUCUUUGGUGAUCUGUCAUAUACAGCAGACAUUACUUGAAACAAAGAAAAAAAUGUUUUAAAACCUGUCUGGAUGAUUUCCGCAGUCUCACUAGGUUAUUGCAGCCAGGGAGUGACCUAGCAGAGAUCUGAAGGUGAGCUUCCCUAGUACUGGCAUCUCACAGUGAAAGAGCACUGUUCAGUGGGUCAAGAGACCCAGAGCCUACUCUCAGUUACGACACACAUAGUCCUUGUGUGGCCUUUCUGGGCUUGUGUCCUGAACUAUAAAAUGAGAGGGUGGCACUAAAUGUUUUUUUCAGAUCUCUAUAGAGGCUGGAAUGGCCACAGAGAAUCUAAAUUUGAAAACAAACAUGUCCUGAGGGUGUGCUCCAAUACCACCCUUUAAUACUCUCCUGAGAUGUGAAGGCUGGAAAUGAGAAUGCCAUAUUAUUGUUACUUGCAAACGAUUAGUGUAUCUGGGACAUCCAAAAGAAGUAACUGAAAAUUUAUUUCUUUAAAAACAAAAAAAACCAUUACAGUGCUUUUGUAAAAACAUUAAUAUUUAGAAGUACGUAGUGGUAAUAAAAGGAAAAUAGUUGUAAGACCUUCAUUAAAAAGAAAAACCUAAAAAAAAAAACAAAACAAAACUCUGGAUACAGGUGUAUGAUUUACCUAACCAGACAUAGCUUUCUUUUGGAUAAAAAAAAAAAAAAAAAAAAAGCUCAGAAGUGCAGAACUGUACAGAUGUCCCUAAAUCUAUUAAUUCAAUGCUAAACGAAAUAAUCUCUUAACAUGAUAAAAUUACACCAAACUUCAUCUGGAAAAAUAAACACGUAAUAAUGAAAAAAGUUAGCCACUCCCACCUCCCCACUUAAAAAAGACAAAUGAAGAAAUACUAGUCCAAGGCCAGGUGUGGUGGCUCACAUCUGUAAUCCCAACACUUUGAGAGGCUGAGGUGGGAGGACUGCUUGAACCCAGGAGUUCAAGACCAGCCUAGGCAUCAUGGCAAAACCCCAUCUCUACAAAAAAUACCAAAAUAAAAAGAAUUAGCUGGGCAUGGUGGCACAUACCUGUAGUCCCAGCUACUUGGGAGGCUGAGGUGAGAGGAUCACUUGAGCCCGGAAGAUCAAGGCGACAGUAAGCCAUGAUGGCACCACUGCACUCCAGCCUGGGUGACAGAAUGAAACCCUGUCUCAAAAAACAAACAAACAAAAACCAAACAAAUUAUAGGAAAAUCAACAUUUUAAACCAAAGAAGAGAAGGAGAAAGAAGGGAAGGGAAGCCAUAAAAGUGUCUUUUUCAAAUAGAUCAUGGGGGAAAAAAAAAAAAAGUAUGACUUGGAAUAGAGACAGCCUUACAAGCAGGAUCUAAAACUCAGAAUCCAUUUUUUUAAAUUGUGAUAAAUUUGACUAUAGAAAAAUGUAAACUUUGGAUACAAAAGUACCAUAUUUAAAGUAAAUAAGCUACAACUAUUACAUGACAGAGAAAAUGUCCUCAAACUUCUAAGGAACUUCUAACAAGUAGAAAAAAAACACACACAACCCCAAAGCAAACACCAAUAGUCAAUAAAUAUAUGAAAGUGUUCAAUGUUACUCAUAAUAAAGGCAUACAAAUCAAACCA